AGGCGUUUGCGAGAGGAGAUACGAGCUGGACGCCUGGCCCUUCCCUCCCACCGGGUCCUAGUCCACCGCUCCCGGCGCCGGCUCCCCGCCUCUCCCGCUAUGUACCGACCGCGAGCCCGGGCGGCUCCCGAGGGCAGGGUCCGGGGCUGCGCGGUGCCCAGCACCGUGCUCCUGCUGCUCGCCUACCUGGCUUACCUGGCGCUGGGCACCGGCGUGUUCUGGACGCUGGAGGGCCGCGCGGCGCAGGACUCCAGCCGCAGCUUCCAGCGCGACAAGUGGGAGCUGUUGCAGAACUUCACGUGUCUGGACCGCCCGGCGCUGGACUCGCUGAUCCGGGAUGUCGUCCAAGCAUACAAAAACGGAGCCAGCCUCCUCAGCAACACCACCAGCAUGGGGCGCUGGGAGCUCGUGGGCUCCUUCUUCUUUUCUGUGUCCACCAUCACCACCAUUGGCUAUGGCAACCUGAGCCCCAACACGAUGGCUGCCCGCCUCUUCUGCAUCUUCUUUGCCCUUGUGGGGAUCCCACUCAACCUCGUGGUGCUCAACCGACUGGGGCAUCUCAUGCAGCAGGGAGUAAACCACUGGGCCAGCAGGCUGGGGGGCACCUGGCAGGAUCCUGACAAGGCGCGGUGGCUGGCGGGCUCUGGCGCCCUCCUCUCGGGCCUCCUGCUCUUCCUGCUGCUGCCACCGCUGCUCUUCUCCCACAUGGAGGGCUGGAGCUACACAGAGGGCUUCUACUUCGCCUUCAUCACCCUCAGCACCGUGGGCUUCGGCGACUACGUGAUUGCAAGCUGCCUCAUUUCAGAUACGAGAAAACCAAACAGAGACUGGCAAACACUAGAGCGGACAUCGAAAUCCUCUGGGGGCUUGUUAAAAUACAGAUUUCUGGCCGGGCACGGUGGCUCACACCUGUAAUUCUAACACUUUGGGAGGCCGAGGAAUGAACCCCUCCCAGAGGUACCCACUGUGGUACAAGAACAUGGUGUCCCUGUGGAUCCUCUUUGGGAUGGCAUGGCUGGCCUUGAUCAUCAAACUCAUCCUCUCCCAGCUGGAGACGCCAGGGAGGGUAUGUUCCUGCUGCCACCACAGCUCUAAGGAAGACUUCAAGUCCCAAAGCUGGAGACAGGGACCUGACCGGGAGCCAGAGUCCCACUCCCCACAGCAAGGAUGCUAUCCAGAGGGACCCAUGGGAAUCAUACAGCAUCUGGAACCUUCUGCUCACGCUGCAGGCUGUGGCAAGGACAGCUAGUUAUACUCCAUUCUUUGGUCGUCGUCCUCGGUAGCAAGACCCCUGAUUUUAAGCUUUGCACAUGUCCACCCAAACUAAAGACUACAUUUUCCAUCCACCCUAGAGGCUGGGUGCAGCUAUAUGAUUAAUUCUGCCCAAUAGGGUAUACAGAGACAUGUCCUGGGUGACAUGGGAUGUGACUUUCGGGUGUCGGGGCAGCAUGCCCUUCUCCCCCACUUCCUUACUUUAGCGGGCUGCAAUGCCGCCGAUAUGAUGGCUGGGAGCUCUGGCAGCCAUACGGCACCAUGAAGUAGCGGCAAUGUUUGAGCGGCACAAUAAGAUAGGAAGAGUCUGGAUCUCUGAUGAUCACAGAGCCAUCCUAACAAACGGAAUAUCACCCGACCUCCUUUAUGUGAGAGAGAAAUAAACAUCUUAUGUAAAAUACCA